AGACUUGUCUCUCCAGAAUGACUAUCCUCCAUUUCUAGGUCCCAAAUCACAACCAUGAAGUUGAUCUUAUGGUACUUGGUUGUGGCACUUUGGUGCUUCUUCAAAGAUGUGGAAGCCUUACUUUACCGACAAAAAUCAGAUGGUAAAAUAGCAGCAAGCAGAUCAGGUGGCUUCUCUUAUGGUAGUUCAUCCUCUGGUGACUUGGACAGAAAAAAGCCACUCUUUAGCUUGGAAUUUGGUUCUCCAGGAGAGACUGAAGACAAGUCCAGACAACGUCAGGAUGCUGGGAGUCCAAAGUCAGAAGACACCCCAGCAGGUGGCUUUUUUAACAGUAGUUCAUCCUCCGGUGACUCAGACAGGACAAAGCCAUUCUUUAGCUUAGGACUUGGUGCUCCAGGAAAGGCUGAAGACAAGUCCGGAGACAGUCAGGAUGCUGGAGGUUCAAAGUCAGAAGACACCCCACCAGGUGGCUUUUUUUAUGGUAGUUCAUCCUCUGGUGACUCAGACAAAAAAAAGCCACUCUUUAGCUUUGAAUUUGGUGCUACAGGAGAGGAUGAAGACAAGUCCAGAGAACGCUGGGAUGCUGGGAAUUCAAGGUCAGAAGACAGCCCAGCAGAUAGCACCAACACAAGAUAUGGUGCUGGCUUUAGUAGCAGUGGUGCCUCUCUGGAUGUGGGAUUUGGUUGGGGGAUAUCUGAUGAAAAGGGAUUGGAAGUCAGUAAAGCUGAUGGGAGAGAAACUAGAGGCAGUGGAUCUGCUGGGGGUGAAACCAUAGUCUUUGGACCUGAUGCAGGUAGCUCAGUUGGAACUGGUUCUUCUGGUUUGAAACUUGGAGCAGGGAAAGGUGAUGCUGCAUUUGGUUUUGAAGUUUCUGAUUCGAAUUCAUUUGGUGACACUGGCAUUAGUAGCAAAACAGUUGAAGGAAAUCAAACGAGUAGUUCUGGAGGAUCUGUUUCCAUUGAUCUAGGUGAUACCAGUUUCAGAAGUGAGAAUCAAUUUGUUGGUGGUGGCUCUCUAAAUUCGAUAUCCAAUUUAUGGGAUUCUGGUCAAGAGGGAUUUGGAAUCAAUGAAAUUGGAGGGAAUGGAAUGAGUGGCAGUGUAUCUGCUGAGGCUGGAUUCAAAGGUUUUGGAUCUGAUUCAAGUAGCUCAGGUGAUUCAAGUGCAAGAAAUGGGUUUGAAAAUUCUAGUGGUAUCUCUGAAGAUUCAGGAGUCAUAUUGGGGUCAUCUGAUCAACAUGAAGUUGAACUCAGUAGAACUGGUGGGAAUAGAAAGAGAAGCAGUGACCCUGAUGAGGCUGGAAACUUGAGUCCUGGAUCUGAUGUCAGUGACUCAGGAGGAAACACUUGGUCUUCUGAUUCUGGAAGUGGUGGAGGAGGUGUCACAAGCUCGUCUGAAUAUAGUACGUCUGGACCACUCAAUACUCCAGAAAAAGGAUCCCACAUUCCAGAAGCAACUCCAAAAUACUCAGAAACAAAUGCAAUUAUUGGUGAAAUAUCUACCUGGAGCAAAGGAGCAUAUAAAUCUUUCAACGGCCGCAUCUUUUUCUUUGAAUCUUCAUGCCCAUACACUUUCUGCCGUCACUGCAUUGAAUCUGGAGGGGAUUUCAAUAUUGAGAUCAAACGAAACAAUGAUAGUGAGAUUGAAAAAAUAACAGUUCUAAUUGACAAUAACGACGUCUCUAUUUUUGGUGACACCAUUUUAGUUAAUGGAGAAAGUGUACAGAUACCAUAUAACAAUAAGUUGAUUCACAUAAAAAAAUAUGGAGAACAUAAUGUUCUGAAUAGCCGUAGAGGAAUCCUGACUUUAAUGUGGGACAAAAAUAACAAACUCUCGCUCACUCUUCACAAGCAGUAUCCAACUUGUGGUCUUUGUGGUAACUUCAACAGCACUCCAGGGCAAGAUAUUAAUGAGCACAUUGCCAAUAGUAAAAUUCCUGGUGAUUGUCCCAAUGCUGUUGGUAAAAGCUAUGAAGUUUGUGAAGAUGGAAUACAGCACUGUAACAAAAUUAUUGGAACCUACUUUGAGAAAUGUGGAAAGGUUGCUGCUCUAUCCAAUGACUACAAAAUGAUCUGCAUUGAUGAAUACUGCCAAACUAGAGACAAAACAUCUACAUGUGACACUUAUUCAGAACUGUCCCGCCUCUGUGCCUCAGAUGGUCCUGGCACCUUUGAAUCCUGGCGAAGCGACUCCGAUGUGGUUUGUGGAACACAAAGAUGUCCAGAACAACAUAUCUACAAAGAAUGUGGACCCUCCAACCCUGCAACUUGUUCUAAUGUGGCUCCUUUUCAAGACAGUGAAUGUGUGAGCGGCUGCACCUGCCCAGAAGGUUAUCUGUUGGAUGACAUUGGAGAGAAAGGAAAAUGUGUAUUAAAAGCUGAAUGUCCCUGUGAAUCCAGUGGAACAGUGUAUCAGCCAGGAGAAGUCCGAGAAGGUCCUUGUGGUUCUCAGUGCACAUGCCAAGAUGCAAAGUGGUCUUGCACCGAAGCAUUAUGCCCUGGAAGAUGUAAGGUGGAAGGAAGUUCCCUUACCACCUUUGAUGGUGUUAAGUACAACUUUCCUGGAAACUGCCACUUCCUGGCCGUUCACAAUGAAGAUUGGUCUAUUAGUGUUGAGCUCCGUCCGUGCCCAAGUGGUCAGACAGGAACGUGCUUAAAUAGCGUUACACUUCUCUUGAAUUCUUCUGUUCCAGUUGACAAAUACGUAUUCAACAGUGAUGGAACAGUCACAAAUGACAAGAUUAGAAAUCAAGGUUAUUACUAUUCAGAUAAAAUACAGAUAUUCAAUGCAUCUUCCUCAUACCUUCAAGUAGAAACAUACUUUCAUGUGAAACUACAAAUACAAAUUGUUCCUGUGAUGCAAUUGUAUGUUUCUAUGCCACCCAACCAAUUCACAGACACUGUGGGACUCUGUGGUUCCUACAACAACAAAGCAGAGGAUGAUUUCAUGUCAAGUCAGAAUAUAUUGGAGAAGACAUCUCAGGCAUUUGCUAACUCUUGGGAAAUGAUGUCCUGUCCUAAAGGAAACCCCUCUUCAUGUAUUAGUAUAGAAAAAGAAAAAUUUGCUGAAAGGCACUGUGGAAUUCUUCUUGAUUCAAGUGGGCCUUUGGCUUCCUGCCACCCAAUUGUGAACCCUAAACCCUAUCAUGAGGAAUGCAAAAAAUAUACUUGCACUUGUGAAAACAGUCAGGACUGCCUAUGUACAAUUUUAGGCAACUAUGUGAAAGCGUGUGCUGAGAAGGAAACAUACAUAGUGGGAUGGAGAACUGGCCUAUGUGAACAUUCUUGCCCAAGUGGCCUAGUGUUCAAGUACAAUGUAAAAGCCUGUAAUAGUUCUUGCCGAUCCUUGUCAGAAAGAGAUAGGAGCUGUGAUGUAGAAGAUGUUCCAGUUGAUGGAUGCACCUGCCCUGAUGCAAUGUACCAGAAUAAUGAAGGAAACUGUGUACUGAAAUCUCAGUGUGACUGUUACAUAAACGACGAGGUCAUGCAACCAGGCAAACUCAUCCAUAUUGAUGACAAUAAAUGCGUCUGUCGGGAUGGAAUUCUUCUUUGCCAGAUUCCCAUUGAUUUAACCCUACAAAAUUGUUCUGGAGGGGCUGAGUAUGUAGACUGCAGUGAUCCCAAGGCACAGAGAAGAACCAACAGAACAUGCAGUACUCGGAACAUACCUGUUUUUGAUGAGAACUUGCCUUGCAAACGUGGGUGCUUUUGUCCAGAAGGAAUGGUUCGAAAUUCUAAAGGGAUAUGUGUCUUUCCUAAUGACUGUCCAUGCUCUUUUGGUGGACGAGAAUAUGAUGAAGGAAGUGUCACUUCUGUUGGCUGCAAUGAAUGUACCUGCAUUAAAGGGUCUUGGAGUUGUACCCAAAAUGAAUGUCAAACCAUCUGCCACAUCUAUGGGGAAGGUCAUGUUAGAACUUUUGAUGGGAAGAGUUACAGUUUUGACGGUCUCUGCCAGUAUUCAUUUCUUGAGGAUUAUUGUGGUCAUGAAAAUGGCACAUUUCGUAUUUUAACGGAGAGUGUUCCAUGCUGUGAAGAUGGGCUAACGUGCUCAAGAAAAAUUAUAGUUGCUUUUCAGGAUCAGAAUAUUGUCUUGCAAGACGGUAAAGUAACAGCAGUCAAAUCUACAGAAAGUAAGAAAUGUGAACUCAAUGCAAAUGCAUACUCCAUACAUACUGUUGGCCUGUACUUAAUUCUGAAAUUUCAAAAUGGAAUAAUCGUGAUUUGGGACAAAAAUACAAGACUGUCUGUUAUUCUGGAUCCAAACUGGAAUGGCAAAGUGUGUGGUCUUUGUGGAAAUAACAAUGGUGAUCUCAAGGAUGAUUUCACAACAAGAUACUCUUCAGUAGCUUCUGGAGCACUGGAAUUUGGGAAUAGUUGGAAAACAAGCCAAGAAUGUUCAGAUACAGUGGCUCAGACUUUCCCAUGUGAUUCAAACCCAUACUGUAAAGCCUGGGCUGUGCGGAAAUGUGAGAUCCUCAGAGACAGCACCUUCAGAGACUGCCACAACAAGGUUGACCCCAGUGCUUACCAUGAUGUGUGCAUUGAAGAAGCCUGUGCAUGUGACAUGGAGGGGAAGUACCUGGGAUUCUGCACUGCCGUGGCUAUGUACGCAGAGGCGUGUAGUGCAGUUGGAGUCUGUGUCUCAUGGAGAAAACCAAAUCUGUGUCCUGUCUACUGUGAUUACUACAAUGCGCCUGGGGAAUGCAGAUGGCAUUAUGAACCUUGUGGCACAGUGACUGCAAAAACAUGCAAAGAUCAGCUCGUUGGCCAGAAAUUUUCUUCACUUUUAGAAGGUUGUUAUGCUAAGUGCCCAGAUAGUGCUCCUUACUUGGAUGAGAACACCAUGAAAUGUGUCAGUUUAUCUGAGUGCAGCUGUUUCUAUAAUGAUGUCAUACCAGCAGGGGGAGUGAUUGAAGAUAAUUGUGGAAGAACAUGCUACUGCAUUGCAGGGCAGUUGGAGUGCAGUGAAACUGCUCCUACCAAUUCAACAUUUGCAGUUUCCACUACAACAGCUACCACCAUAUUAAGCACCGGAGCAGCAAUUACACUGGUUACCGGUGGCCCAAGCACAGCAGCAUCCAUUCCAGCGAUUACAACAUCAAGCAGUGAAACAACAGGAACAACUCUAGGUCCUCUCACCGAACCUUUUACUACAGGCAUUACUGAAACUUCAGUUCCCAUCAUCUCAACAUCUGGAAAUGCAGGCAUGACAGGAGUAGUGAGCCCCACCGUCACUGGUGCUUCAGGCAUGGCAGGAACAACUGGAGGAGUGGAUGCAGCCACCACUGGAGCUGCUAGUGAAAAUACAUCUGAGAGAGCAGGCACACCGAGGGUAUCUGGAGAAACCCCUGCAGUCGGAGGUGGCAGUACCCCUGGAGAAGCAGGCCCUGGAGCCACAGUUUCUGGAAGUACAGGAGUUUCUGCAGGCUCCAUCACUGCCAGCCCUGGAGCCUCAGCCACAAGCUCUGAAAGCAGCAAAUCAGGAACUACUGGACCCUCAGUGGGUGGAAAAACUGGAGCCACAAGCAGUGAAGCGACAUCAUCUGAAGGCAUGUCAGGUGUAACAGGACAGUCUCUUGGAUCUACUGCUGGAUCUGACAGUGAAAUCACAGCUAAAACAUCUUUCACUGGUUCCAGUCCACCUGGGAAACUCACCAGGCCAAGCCCGGGCUCACCUGGUCACUUUAGUGGUGGAACAACUGAAUGGGGAAAUGUAGCCACCACUGGAGCUGCUGGUGAAAACACUUCUGGAGCAUUGGGUUCAACAGAAGGGUCUGUGGAAGCCACCACCAGCGCAGGCAGUGGAAACACAGCUGGAACAUCAGGUACUGGGGACACUGGCCCUGGUAACACAGCAGUCUCAGGCACACCUGUGGUAUCACCUGGAGCAACUCCUGGAGCUCCAGGUAGCAGCACCCCUGGGGAAGCAGACAUUGGAAACACCAGUUUUGGAAAAUCAGGGACCCCAACAGUAUCUGCUGCCUCAACUACCAGUAGCCCUGUGAGUAAACACACCGAUGCAGCCUCAGCCACAGCAGUGACAAUCUCUGGAAGCAAACCAGGUACACCUGGAACACCAGGUGGUGCAACUAGUGGAGGCAAAAUUACAUCUGGAUGGUCCAGCAGUGGCACCAGCACGGGCGCUUCAAAUACACCAGGGGCAACAGGAUCAUCGACCGGACAGACAGACACAAGUGGACCAUCAGCUAAAGUAACAGGGAAUUAUGGACAAUCAUCUGAAAUACCAGGGACAAUUAAAUCAUCAUCUGAUGUUUCAGGGACAAUGGGGCAAUCAGAUACAACAUCUGGACCAUCAGUUGCAGUGACAAGGACUUCUGAACAAUCGUCAGGAGUCACGGUGGCAUCUGAACCAUCAGUUGGAGUAUCAGGGACAACUGGACCAUUAGCUGAAAUAUCAGGGACAACCAGACCAUUAGUUUCAGGGUUAAGGACAACUGGAUCAUCAGCUGAAGGAUCAGGGACAACUGGACCUUCAUCAAGAGAAUCAGUGACAACUAGACCAUUAGCUGAAGGUUCAGGGACAAGUGGACAAUCGGUUACAGGAUCAAGAGCAACUGGAUUAUCAGCUACAGAAUUAGGGACAACUGUGUCUUUUACUGGAGGAUUAGGUACAAGUAGAUCAUCUGCUAGAGAAACAAGGACAACUGGACCAUCAGCUGACGGGUCAGGAACAACUGGACCAUCUGUUGUGAGAUCAGGGACAACUAGAUUAUCAGUUGGAGUGACAAGAGCAACUGAAUCAUCACCUGGAGUGACAGGAACAACUACACCAUCAGCUGAAGAAUCCAGGACAACAGGACCAUCUGUUCUAGUGACAGGAACAACUGGACAAUCAGGCCAAGGAUCAGGGACAACUGGAAAAUCUUUUAUAGAAUCAGGACCAUCUGUUGUAGGAUCAGGGACAACUGGACCAACAUCUGCAGGAUUAGGAACAACUGCACCAUCAACCAGAAGAUCAAGCACAACAAAACCAUCAGUUGGAAGAACUGGGACAACUGGACAAUCAGGUGCAGAAUCAGGAACAACUGAACCAUCAGCUAGAGUGGCAGGUGUAACUGGAACAUCAGCUGAAGUAUCAGGAAGAAUUGAACCAUCAGCUACAGAAUCAAGUACAAGUAGACCACUAGGUGAAACAACAGGGACAACUAUACCAUCAAUGGAAGGAUCAGAGGCAACUGGACCAUCUGUCAUUGGAUCAGAAACAACUAGACUAUCAGUUAUAGGAUCAGGGACAACUGGAACUUCAUCUGGAGGUUCAGGUGCAACAAGAUCAUCAGGUGGAGGAAUGGGGACAACUGGACAAUCAACUGCAAGAUCAGAAACAACUGGACCACUUUUUGGAUUGACAGGAACAUUUGGGCAAUCUGCUACAGUGACUGGGACAUCUUCAAAUUCAGCUGGAGUGACAACACCUGAAAAAUCACCUGGAGUGGCAAUGACAACAGGACUGUUGGUUGAAGGAUCAGCUACAACUCAACCACGUAUUUUAGAAUCAGAAACAACUGAAUCAUCAGCUGGAGUGAUAGUGACAUCUGGACAAUCAGCCAGAGUGACUGGGGCAACUGGACCAUCAGCUGGAGAGACAGGAACAACUGAACCAUCAACUGAAGGAUCAGUUGCAGCUGUAUUAUUUGUUAUUGGAUCAGAAACAACUAGACCAUUAGAUAUAGGAUCAGGGACAACUGGAACUUUAUCUGGAGGUUCAAGUACAACAAGAUCAUCAGAUGGAACAACAGGGACAACCAGAAAAUCAACUGCAAGAUCAGAAACAACUGGACUUUCUGGAUUGACAGGAACAUCUGGGCAAUUGGCUGGAGUGACUGGGACAUCUUCAAAAUCAGCUGGAGUAACAGUGACAUCUGAAAAAUCAGCUGGAGUUGCAGUGAUAACAGGAUCAUUUGUUGAAAGACCAGUCACAACUGGACCACCUCUUUUAGAAUCAGAGACAACUAGACCAUCAGGUGGAGUAACAGUGACAUCUGGACAAUCAGCCAGAGUGACUGAAACAGUUGGAGCAUCAGCUGGAGUGACAGGAACAACUGGACCAUCAACUGAAGGAUCAGGGGCAACUGGACCAUCUGUUGUGGGAUCAGGAACAACUAGACCAUUAGCUGGUGAAUCAGGUACAACUGAGUCAUCAGCUGGAGUGACAGGGACAAGGCCAUCAUCAUCAAGAGAAUCAGCAACAACUGGACCAUCAGAUGAAGGAUCAGGAACAACUGGACUAUCAGCUGGAGUGACAGUGACAUCUGGACAAUCAGUUAGAAAGACUGGGACAACUGGAGCACCAGCUGGAGUUACAGAAACAACAAGACCAUCUGUUGUCAAAUCAGGGACAACUGGACCAUCUGUUAUAGGAACGAGGACAACUGGAACUUCAUCAGGAGGAUCAGGUGCAACAAGAUCAUCAGGUGGAGAAACAGAGACAACUGGCCAAUCAGCUGUAAAAUCAGGGACAACAGAAUCAUUUACUAGGUUGACAAGAACAUCUGGGCAAUCAGCUGGAAUGACUGGGACAUCUGCACAAUCAGCUGGAGUGGCACUAACAAGUCCUUUUGUUGAAGGAUUAGUGACAACUGGAUCAUCUACUGUAGGAUUAGAGACAACUAGACCUUCAGCUGUAGGAUCAGGAAAAACUGGACCUCCUGUUGUAAAAGCACAGACAACUGGACCAUCAGCUGGAGUGACAGUGACAUCCGGACAAUCAGCUAGAAUGACUGGGGCAAGUGGACCAUCAGUAGGAGUGACAGGAACAACUGGACCAGCAAGUAAAGGAUUAGGGACAAUUAGACCAUCUGUUGUAGGAUUAGAGACUACUGAACUAUCAGCUGAAGGAUCAGGGACAACUGGACCACCUAUUGUAGGAGAGACAACUGUACCAUCAGCUGGAGUGACAGUUACAUCUGGAUACUCAGAUAGAGUGACUGGGGCAACUGAACCAUUGGCUGGAGUAACAGGAACCAUUAAACCAUCUGUUGCAGGAUCAGUGACAACUGGACCAUCUGUUACAGGAGUAGAGACAACUGCAAAAACUACAUCUGGAGGAUUAAGUACAACUAUAUCGUCAGUUGGAGGAACAGGGACCACUGGACAAUCACCUGAAAGAUCAGGGACAACAGGACCAUUUACUGGAUUGACAGGGACAUCUGCACAAUCAGCUGGAGUCACAAUGACAUCUAUCCAAUCAGCUGGAGUGCUAGUAACAACAGGACUAAAUGUUGAUGGCUUAGGGACAACUGGAAAAGCUCUUAUAGGAUCAGGAACAACUGGAUUAUCAGCUGAAGCUACAGGGACAAUUGGACCAUCAACUGAAGGAUUAGAGAAAACUGGACCAUCUAUUACUGGAUCAGGAACAACCAGACCAUUAGUUACAGAAUCAUGGACAGCUGGAACUUCAUCUGGAGGACAUAGUACAACAAGUCCAUCAGUUAGAGGAACAGAGACAACUGGACAAUCAGCUGCAGAAUCAGUGACAACAGGGCCAGUUACAGGAUACACAGAAACCUCUGGUCCAUCAGCUGGAGUGACAGUGACACCUCGGCAAUCACCUACAGUGACUCAGACAACUGGAUCAUCAGCUGCAGUAUCAGGGACAACUGUACAAUCUCUUACAGUAUCAGGGACCACUAGACCAUCAUCUGGACAAACAGAAAUAACUGGAUCGUCAGUUAAAGAAUCAGGGACAACUGAAUCAUCAGCUGUAAGGUCAGGGACUACUGGACCAACAGCUGGAGUGACAGGUACAAAUGGACCAUCAUCAGCUGGAGUGACAGGGAUAACUGGAUCAUCACCUGGAGUGACAGGGACAACUGGAUCAUCACCUGGAGUGACAGGGACAACUGGAUCAUCUGCAAGAUCAGGGACAAGUAUACCAUCAGUUGGAAAAACAGGAACGACUAGAACAUCAGUUGAAGAAUCAAGGACAACUAGACCAUCAGCUGGAAUAACAGGUACAAAUGGACUAUCAGCUGAAGUGACAGGGACAACUGGACCAUUAGCUGGAGUGACAGGGACAACUGGACCAUCAGCUGGAGUGACAAGGACAACUGGACUGUCAGCUGGAGAGACAGGGACAACUGGACUAUCACCUGGAGUGACAAGGACAACAAGAUCAUCAGCUGGGCUAACAGGGAAAACAGGACUAUCAGCUGGGGUGACAGGGAAAACUGGACUGUCAGCUGAAGUGACAGGGACAACUAGACUAUCAGCUGGAGUGACAGGGACAACUGGACCAUCACCUGGAGUAACAGGUACAACUGGAACACCAGCUGGGGUUACAGGGACAACUGAACUAUCAGCUGGAGUGACAGGGAAAACUGGACUAUCAUCUGAAGUGACAGAAACAACUGGAUUAUCAUAUGGGGUGAAAAGGACAAUUGGACUAUCAGCUGGGUCGACAGGGACAAGUGGACAAUCAGCUGGAGUGGCAGGGACAACUACACUAUCAGCUGAAGUGACAGGGACAACUAGACCAUCAGCUGGGGUAACAGGGACAACAGGACUAUCAGCUGAAGUGACAGAGAUAACUGGAAUAUCAGCUGUGGUGACAGGGACAACUGGACCAUCAGCUGGGGUGACAGAGACAACUGGAUCAUCAGCUGGAGUGGCAGGGACAACAAGACUAUCAGCUGGAGUGACAGGGAUAACUGGACUAUCAGCUGGAGUGACAGGGACAACUGGACUGUCAACUGAAGUGACAGGGACAACUGGACCAUCAGCUGGGGCGACAGGGACAACUGGACUAUCAGUUGGAGUGACUGGGAUAACUGGGCUAUCAGAUGUAGUGACAGAGACAACUGGAUCAUCUGCAAGAUCAGGGACAGGUAUACCAUCAGUUGGAGAAACAAGAACAACUAGCACAUCAGUUGAAGAAUCAAGGACAACUAGACCAUCAGCUGGAAUAAUGGGUACAAAUGGACUACCAGCUGAAGUGACAGGGACAACUGAACCAUUAGCUGGAGGGACAGGGACAACUGGAAUAUUAGCCGGGGUGACAGGGACAACUGGACUAUCAGCUGGGGAGACAGGGAAAAUUGGAUCAUCAGCUGGGGUGACAGGGAAAACUGGAUCAUCAGCAAGAGUGACAGGAAAAACUGGACCAUCAGCAGAAGUAACAGGGAAAACUGGACUAUCAGCUGGAGUGACGGGGACAACUGGACUAUCACCUGGAGUGACAGGGACAAGUGGACUAUCAGCUGAAGUGACAGGGACAACUGGCCCAUCAGCUGAAGCUACAGGGCUACCUGGAGUAUCAGCUGGGGUGACAGGGACAACUGGAUCACUAGCUGGAGGGACAGGGACAAUUGGACUAUCAGCUGGGGUGACAGGGACAACUGGAUCAUCAGCUGGGGUGACAGGGACAACUGGACUAUCAGCUGGGGUGACAGGGAUAGCUGGACUCUCAGCUGGGGUGACAGGGAUAACUGGACCAUCAGCUGGAGUGACAGGGACAACUACAGUAUCAGCUGGAGUAACAGGGACAACUGGACUAUCAGCUGAAGCAACAGAGAUAACUGGACUAUCAGCUGGGGUGACAGGGACAACUGGACUAUCUGCUGGGGUGACAGAGACAAUUAGACUAUCAGCUGGGGUGACAGGGACAAUUAGAUCAUCAGCUGGGGUAACAGGGAUAACUGGACUAUCAGCUGGAGUGACAGGGACAACUGGACCAUCAGCUGGUGUGACAGGGUCAACUGGACUAUUAGCUGGGGUGACAGAGACAACUGGACAGUCAGCUAAAGUGACAGGGACAACUGGACAAUCUGUCGGAGUGACAGGGACAACUAGAUCAUCAGGUGGAGUGACAGGGAUAACUGGACUAUCAGCUGGAGUGACAGGGACAAAUGGACUAUCAGCUGUGACAGGAAUGACUGGACUAUCAGCUGAGGUGACAGGGACAACUGGACUAUCAGUUGGGGUGACAGGGAUAGCUGGACUCUCAGCUGGCGUGACAGGGAUAACUGGACCAUCAGCUGGAAUAACAGGGACAACUACCAUAUCAGCUGGAGUAACAGGGACAAGUGGACUAUCAGCUGAAGCAACAGGGAUAACUGGACUAUCGGCUGGGGUGACAGGGAAAACUGGACUAUCUGCUGGAGUGACAGAGACAAUUGGACUAUCAGCUGAAGCGACAGGGACAAUUGGAUCAUCACCUGGGGUGACAGGGACAACUGGAUCAUCAACUGGGGUGACAGGGAUAACUGGAUUAUCAGCUGGAGUGACAGGGACAACUGGAUUGUCAACUGAAGUGACAGGAACAACUGGACCAUCAGCUGGGGUGACAAGGACUACUGGACUAUCAGCUGGAGUGACUGGGAUAACUGGGCUAUCAGCUAUAGUGACAGAGACAACUGGAUCAUCCGCAAGAUCAGGGACAAGUAUCCCAUCAGUUGGAGAAACAGGAACAACUAGAACAUCAGUUGAAGAAUCAAGGACAACUAGACCAUCAGCUGGAAUAACGGGUACAAAUGGACUAUCAGCUGAAGUGAGGACAAUUGGACCAUUAGCUGGAGGGACAGGGACAACUGGACUAUCAGCUGGGGUGACAGGAACAGUUGGAUCAUCAGCUGUGGUAACAGGGACAACUGGACUAUCAGCUGGAGUCACAGGGACAACUGGACCAUCAGCUGAAGAGACAGGGGCAACUGGACCAUCAGCCGAAGUGACAGAGACAACUGGACCAUCAGCUGGGGUGACAGGGACAGGUAGACUAUCAGCUGAAGUGACAGGGACAACUGGCCCAUCAGCUGAAGUAACAGGGCUACCUGGAGAAUCAGCUGAGGUGACAGGGACAAUUGGAUCACCAGCUGGAGUGACAGGGACAACUCAGCUAUCAGCUGUGGUGACAGGGAUAACUGGACUAUCAGCUGAGGUGACAGGGACAACUGGACUAUCAGCUGGGGUGACAGGGAUAACUGGACUAUCAGCUGAGGUGACAAGGACAACUGGACUAUCAGCUGGGGUGACAGGGACAAUUGGACUAUCAGCUGGGGUGACAGGGACAACCAGACCAUCAGCUGGAGUGACAGGGACAACUGGACAAUCAGCUGAAGUGACAGGGACAACUGAACCAUCAGCUGGGUUGACAGAGACAACUGGAUCAUCAACUGGGGUGACAGGGGCAACUGGACCAUUAGCUGGAGUGACAGGGACAACUGGAAUAUCAACUGAAGUGACAGGGACAACUGGACCAUCAGCUAGGGUGACAGGGACAACUGUACUAUCAGCUGGAGUGACUGGGAUAACUGGGCUAUCAGCUAUAGUGACAGAGACAACUGGAUCAUCUGCAAGAUCAGGGACAAGUACACCAUCAGUUGGAGAAACAGGAACAACUAGAACAUCGGUUGAAGAAUCAAGGGCAACCAGACCAUCAGCAGGAAUAACAGGUACAAAUGGACAAUCAGCUGAAGUGACAUGGAUAACUGGACCAUUAGCUGGAGUGACAGGGACAACUGGAAUAUCAGCUGGGGUGACAGGGACAACUGGACUGUCAGCUGGGGUGACAGGGACUAUUGGAUCAUCAGCUGUGGUGACAGGUAUAAAUGGACUAUCAGCAGGAGUGACAGGGACAACUGGACCAUCAGCUGAAGAGACAGGGGCAACUGGACCAUCAGCUGAAGUCACAGGGACAACUGGACCAUCAGCUGAAGAGACAGGGGCAACUGGACCAUCAGCUGAAGUCACAGGGACAACUGGACCAUCAGGUGGAGUGACAGGGACAAAUGGACUAUCAGCUGAAGUGACAGGAACAACUGGCCCAUCAGCUGAAGUGACAGGGCUACCUGGAGUAUCAGCUGGGGUGACAGGGACAAUUGGAUCACCAGCUGCAGUGACAGGGACAAUUCGGCCAUCAGCUGUGGUGACAGGGAUAACUGGCCUAUCAGCUGAGGUGACAGGGACAACUGGACUAUCAGCUUGGGUGACAGGGAUAGCUGGACUCUCAGCUGGGGUGACAGAGACAAUUGGAUCAUCAGCUGGGGUGACAGGUACAAAUGGACUAUCAGCUGAAGCAACAGGGACAACUGGACCAUCAGCUGGAGUGACAGGGACAACUGGACUAUCAGCUGGGGUGACAGGGACAGCUGGACUAUCAGCUAGGGUGACAGAGAGUACAGGACUAUCAGCUGGGGUGACAGGGACAACUGGACUAUCAGCAGGAGUGACAGGGACAACUGGACCAUCAGCUGGAAUAACAGGUACAAAUGGACUAUCAGCUGAAGUGACAGGGACAACUGGACCAUUAGCUGGAGUGACAGGGACAAUUGGACUAUCAGCUGGGGUGACAGGGAUAGCUGGACUCUCAGCUGGGGUAACAGAGAGUACUGGACUAUCAGCUGGGGUGACAGGGACAAUUAGAUCAUCAGCUGUGGUGACAGGUAUAAAUGGACUAUCAGCAGGAGUGACAGGGACCACUGGACCAUCAGCUGAAGAGACAGGGGCAACUGGACCAUCAGCUGAAGUCACAGGGACAACUGGACCAUCAGGUGGAGUGACAGGGACAAGUGGAAUAUCAGCUGAAGUGACAGGAACAACUGGCCCAUCAGCUGAAGUGACAGGGCUACCUGGAGUAUCAGCUGGGGUGACAGGGACAAUUGGAUCACCAGCUGCAGUGACAGGGACAACUCGGCCAUCAGCUGUGGUGACAGGGAUAAGUGGACUAUCAGCUGAGGUGACAGGGACAACUGGACUAUCAGCUGGGGUGACAGAGACAAUUGGAUCAUCAGCUGGGGUGACAGGUACAAAUGGACUAUCAGCUGAAGCAACAGAGACAACCGGACCAUCAGCUGGAGUUACAGGGACAACAGGACUAUCAGCUGGGGUGACAGGGACAACUGGACCAUCAGCUGGAAUAGCAGGUACAAAUGGACUAUCAGCUGGGGUGACAGGGACAACUGGACUAUCAGCUAGGGUGACAGAGAGUACUGGACUAUCAGCUGGGGUGACAGGGACAAUUGGAUCAUCAGCUGUGGUGACAGAGACAACUAGACUUUCAUCUGGAGUCACAGGGACAAUUGGACCAUCAGCUGAAGAGACAGGGGCAACUGGACUAUCAGCAGAAGUGACAGGGACAACUGGAUCAUUAGCUGAAGUGACAGGGACAACUGGGCUAUCAGCUGGGGUGACAGGGACAAUUGGAUCAUCAGCUGUGGUGACAGGGACAACUGGACUAUCAGCUGGAAUAACAGGUACAAAUGGACUAUCAGCUGAAGUGACAGGGACAGCUGGACCAUUAGCUGGAGUGACAGGGACAACUGGACUAUCAGCUGGGGUGACAGGGACAACUGGACUAUCAGCUGGGGUGACAGAGACAACUGGACAAUCAGCUGGGGUGACAGAGAGUACUGGACUAUCACCUGGGGUGACAGGGACAAUUGGAUCAUCGGCUGUGGUGACAGGGAUAAAGGGACUAUCAGCAGGAGUGACAGGGACCACUGGACCAUCAGCUGAAGAGACAGGGGCAACUGGACCAUCAGCUGAAGUCACAGGGACAACUGGACCAUCGGGUGGAGUGACAGGGACAAGUGUACUAUCAGUUGAAGUGACAGGAACAACUGGCCCAUCAGCUGAAGUGACAGGGCUACCUGGAGUAUCAGCUGGGUUGACAGGGACAAUUGGAUCACCAGCUGCAGUGAGAGGGACAACUUGGCCAUCAGCUGUGGUGACAGGGAUAAGUGGACUAUCAGGUGAGGUGACAGGGACAACUGGACUAUCAGCUGGGGUGACAGGGAUAGGUGGACUCUCAGCUGGGGUGACAGGGACAAUUGGAUCAUCAGCUGGGGUGACAGGUACAAAUGCACUAUCAGCUGAAGCAACAGGGACAACUGGACCAUCAGCUGGAGUGACAGGGACAACUGGACUAUCAGCUGGGGUGACAGGGACAACUGGACUAUCAGCUGGGGUGACAGGGACAAUUAGAUCAUCAGCUGUGGUGACAGAGACAACUGGACUAUCAGCAGGAGUGACAGGGACAACUGGACCAUCAGCUGGAAUAGCAGGUACAAAUGGACUAUCAGCUGAAGUGACAGGGACAACUGGACUAUCAGCUGGGAUGACAGGGACAACUGGACUAUCAGCUAGGGUGACAGAGAGUACUGGACUAUCAGCUGGGGUGACAGGGACAAUUGGAUCAUCAGCUGUGGUGACAGAGACAACUAGACUAUCAGCUGGAGUCACAGGGACAAUUGGACCAUCAGCUGAAGAGACAGGGGCAACUGGACUAUCAGCAGAAGUGACAAGGACAACUGGAUCAUUAGCUGGAGUGACAGGGACAACUGGACCAUCAGCUGUAGUGACAGGGAAAACUGAACUAUCAGCAGAAGUGACAGGGACAACUGAACUAUCAGCUGAGGUGACAGAGAAAACUGGACCAUCAGCAGAAGUGACAGGGAAAACUGGGCUAUCAGCUGGAGUGAUGGAGACAACUGGACCAUCAGCUGAAGUGACAGGGACAACUGGAUCAUCAGCUGGGGUGACAGGCACAACUGGACCAUCAGCUGGAGUGACAGGGACAACUGGCCCAUCAGCUGAAGCGACAGGGCUACCUGGAGUAUCAGCUGGGGUGACAGGGACAAUUGGAUCACCAGCUGGAGUGACAGGGACAGCUCGGCUAUCAGCUGUGGUGACAGGGAUAAGUGGACUAUCAGCUGAGGUGACAGGGACAACUGGACUAUCAACUGGGGUGACAGGGAUAGCUGGACACUCAGCUGCGGUGACAGGGAUAACUAGACCAUCAGCUGGAGUGACAGGGACAACCACAGUAUCAGCUGGAGUAACAGGGACAAUUGGACUAUCAGCUGAAGCAACAGGGAUAACUCUACCAUCAGCUGGGGUGACAGAGACAACUGGACUAUCUGCUGGAGUGACAGAAACAAUUGGACUAUCAGCUGGGGUGACAGGGACAAUUGGAUCAUCAGCUGGGGUGACAGAGAUAACUGGACUAUCAGCUGGAGUGACAGGGACAACUGGACCAUCAGCUGGUGUGACAGGGUCAACUGUACUAUCAGCUGGGGUGACAGCGACAACUGGACAAUCUGUUGGAGUAACAGGGACAACUGGACCAUCAGCUGGUGUGACAGGGACAACUGGACUAUCAGCUGGGGUGACAGGGAUAGCUGGACUCUCAGCUGGGGUGACAGGGAUAACUGGACCAUCAGCUGGAGUGACAGGGACAACUACAGUAUCAGCCGGAGUAACAGGGACAACUGGACUAUCAGCUGAAGCAACAGAGAUAACUGGACUAUCAGCUGGGGUGACAGGGACAACUGGACUAUCAGCUGGGGUGACAGGGAUAGCUGGACUCUCAGCUGGGGUGACAGAGACAAUUGGAUCAUCAGCUGGGGUGACAGGUACAAAUGGACUAUCAGCUGAAGCAACAGGGAAAACUGGACCAUCAGCUGGAGUGACAGGGACAACUGGACUAUCAGCUGGAGUGACAGGGACAACUGGACUAUCUGCUGGGGUGACAGAGACAAUUGGACUAUCAGCUGGUGUGACAGGGACUAUUGGAUCAUCAGCUGGAGUGAAAGGGACAACUGGACAGUCAGCUGAAGUGACAGGGGCAACUGGACAAUCUGUUGGAGUGACAGGGACAACUAGAUCAUCAGGUGGAGUGACAGGGAUAACUGGACUAUCAGCAGGAUUGAGAGGGACAACUGUUUCAUCUGCAAAAGCAGGGACAAGUAUACCAUUAACUGGAAAAACAGGAACAACUAGAACAUCAGUUGAAGAAUCAACGACAACUGGACCAUCAGCUGGAAUAACAGGUACAAAUGGACUAUCAGCUGAAAUGACAGGGACAAAUGAACUAUCAGCUGGGGUGACAGGGACAAUUGGAUCAUCAGCUGGAGUGACAGGGACAACUGGACUGUCAGUUGAAGCAACAGUGACAACUGGACUAUCAGCUGGAGUGACAGGGACAACUGUCCCAUUAGCUGGGGUAACAUGGACACCUGGACCAUCUGCUGGAGUGACAGGAAUAGCUGCACUAUCAGCUGGAGUGACAGGGAAAAGUGGACUAUCAGCUGGAGUGACAGGGAAAACAGGACUAUCAGCUGGAGUGACAGGGACAACUGGACCGUCAGCUGAAGCAACAGGGAAAACUGGACUAUCAGCUGGAGUGACAGGGAUCACUGGACCAUUUGCUGAAGUGACAGGGACAACUGGAUUAUCAGCUGGGGUGAUAGGGACCACUGGAUCAUCAGCUGAAGUGACAGGAAUAACUGGACUAUCAGCUGGGGUGACAGGGAAGACUAGAUCAUCAGCUGGAGUAACAGGGACAACUGGAUUAUCUGCAAAAUCUGGGACAAGUAUACCAUCAGCUGGAAAAACAGGAACAACCAAAACAUCAGUUGAAGAAUCAAGGACAACUAGACCAUCAGCUGGAAUAACAGCUACAACUGGAGUGCCUGCUGCAACUUCCCCAGGAGCUGAAGGUGAAAGCAUAGCUUCCACGUCAGUUGCCACGGGAGCCAUCCCUCGGUCAACAAUUGCACCAGGAAGUACCACUACUGGUACCACUGGGGUAACCACUGGCACAACUCUUGCCCCUAGAAGUUUCAACAUAGGAACUUCUGGUGGAAUUUCUGGGAAAACCCUCAAACCUGGAAGUUAUGUCUCAGAGGCUACAACUGCUACAGGGACUCCUGGAGCAGGACCGUCAGGAGGCACCACUAUCAGUUCUCCUGAAGUCAGUACCAUUUCAGAAGUUUCCAACACAGGUAUCACUGGAGUAGGCUCUGAGACAUCUAUUGAAACAGGAAUUUCCAACACAGCUACGACUGGGGUGGCUCCUGGCACAACCCUUGCCCCUGGCAGUUCCAGUACAGAGGCCACAACUUCCAUAGGAGGAAGUGCAUCAACAAGAGGAGGAAUAGCCACAGAAGCCACAGGUUCCACAAGAGGGGUCAGGACCACUGGAUCAGAAGCUCCAGAAGGUACUUCUGGAGAAUUCUCUGGGACAACCAUUUCAUCUGGAGGCUUCCACACAGAAGCCACAACUCUCACAGGAGGUAGGGGCAGUAUUGGAACUGAAUCCAGAGCAGAGUCCACAACUUCCCUACCACAAAGUGCAAAAACAAGAGGUGGAAUACUGACAGUAGGUACCUCUGGUGAAUUCCCAGGGACAACAUUUACAUCUGGAGGUUCCCACACAGAGGCCACAACUUUCACAGGAGACAAGGGCAGUACUGGAACUGAAUCCAGAGCAGCCACCACUAGGGCAACUCCUGGCACAACUCUUGUCCCUGGCAGUUCCAAUACAGGGGCCACAGCUUCCCCAGGUGGAAGUGCAAUGACAAGAGGUAGAAUAACCACCGCUACCACUGGGGCUUUCUCUGGAAAGACUCUCGAAUCUGAGAAUGACAACACAGAGGCCACAAGUUCCACCAGAGGGGUCAGGACCACCAGGUCAGAAGCACCAGGAGGUACUUCUGGUGAAUUCCCUGGGACAAGAAUUACAUCUGGAGGUUCCUACACAGCCACCACCAGGGCAGCUCCUGGCACAACUCUUGCCCCUGGCAGUUCCAACACGGGGGCCACAGCUUCCCUAGGUGGAAGUGCAAUGACAAGAGGUAGAAUAACCACCGCUACCACUGGGGCUUUCUCUGGAAAGACUCUGGAACCUGGGAACAACAACACAGAGGCCACAAGUUCCACCAGAGGGGUCAGGACCACCAGAUCAGAAGCUCCAGGAGAGGCCACAACUCUCACAGGAGACAGGAGCAGUACCGGAAGUGAAUCCAGAACAGCCACCACUGGAGUAGCUCCUGGCACAACUGUUGCCCCUGGCAGUUCCAAGACAGAGGCCACCACUUUCCUAGGAGUAAGUGGAACAACAAACAUUGGAAGAGCCACGGGUGCCACAACUUCCAUAGUAGGGAGUGACACCAGCCAAGCAGAACGUCCAGGAGGUACAACUGUGGUUUCACCUGGAGCCAGCAGCACUUCACAGAGCUCCAGGCCAGGCACCUCUGUCACACCAGACAGUUCAGCAUCUGAAAGUGAAACAGUUACUACAAAAGAAUUCUCUGGGACAACUGCUAUAUCUAGAACUUCCCACACCGGCACCCCUGCAGCCUCAGGAGGCCAAGCAACUGGGAGCCUGACAGCCACCACUGGGGUAGCUCCUGGCACAACUGUUGCACCUGGCAGUUCCAACACAGAGGCCACAACUUCUGUAGGAGAAAGAGAAACAACAAAAGCUGAAAUAAUCACAGGUGACACUGGAGAAUUAUCUGGAACAACCAUUAUAUCUGAAAAUUCCACCACAGCAGGCAUCACUGCAGCAACAGGGAAGCAAGCAGGCACCUCGGAGGUAGCUCCUUCCACAACAGUUGCCCCAGGAAGUUUCAGCACAGCAGCCACAACUUCUCCUGGAGCAAGUGGAACGACUGGGGUUACAACAACUACAAAGACCACAACUUCCCUAGGAGGAAGUGGCACCACUGGAGCAGAAAUAAAAUCAGCCACCACUGGAGCACCAGGAAGUAGGACAGGCACAGCUGGAGUGCCCUCUGCUACAACAGUCUCCCCUGGGAGCUCCAACUCAGAGGCCACAACUUCUGUAGGAGAAAGUGGAAAAACAGGAGCUGAAACAAUCACAGAGGCCACCACUUCCACAGAAGGGACUGGUACUUCUGGAACUGGAUUCAAAACUGGCACCUCAGAGGUAGCUCCUGCCACAACGGUUGCCCCAGGAAGUUUCAGCACAGCAGCCACAACUUCUCCUGGAGCAAGUGGAAUGACUGGGGUUACAACAACUACAAAGACCACAACUUCCCUAGGAGGAAGUGGCACCACUGGAGCAAAAAUAAAAUUAGUAGGAACCACCACUACAGCACCAGAAAGUAGGACAGCUGGAGUGCCCUCUGGUACAAGAGUCACCCCUGGGAGCUCCAACUCAGAGGCCACAACUUCUGUAGAAGAAAGCAGAAUAACAAGAGCCGAAGUAAUCACAGAGGCCACAACUUUCUCAGGAGGCAGCGGGGCCACCUGAGCAGGAUUACCCAGAGGUACCACUGGAGAAUUUUCUGGAACGAACUUUAUAUCUGGAAGUUCUAACACAGAGGCCACCACUUCCACAGAAGGGACAGGUACUUCUGGAACUGGAUUCAAAAUUGCAGGCAUCACUUCUGCCCCAGGGAAACAAGCAGGCACCUCUGGGGUAUCUCUUGCCACAACAGUUGCCCCUGGAAGCUUCAGCACAGCCACAACUUCUUCUGGAGCAAGUGGAAUAACUAGGGCUGGCCCCAACUCAGAGACCACAACUUCCCUAGGAGGAAGUGGUACCACUGGAGCAGAAAUAAAAUCAGCUGCAGUGCCCUCUGGUACAACAGUUGCCCCUGGGAGCUCCAACUCAGAAGCCACAACUUCUGUAGGAGAAAAUGGAAAAACAAGAGGUGAAAUAAUCACAGAUACUACUGAGGGCACCUCUGGCAAAGUUCUGGAACCUGGAAGUGCCCACACAGAGGCCACAACUUUCCCAGGAGGCAGUGGGACUACCCGAGCAGGACCACCAGGAGGUACCACUGGAGAAUUGUCUAGAAUGACCAUUAUACCUGGAAGUUCUAACACAGAGGCCACAACUUCCACAAAAGGGACUGGUACUUCUGGAACUGGCUUCAAAACUGGCACCUCUUGGGUGGCGCCUGGCACAACAGUUUCCCCUGGAAGUUUCAGCACAGCCACAAUUUCCCCUGGAGCAAGUAGAACGACUGGGGCUGCACCUGCCGCAGAAACCACAACUUCCCUAGAAGGAGGUGGCACCACUGGAGCAGAAAUAAAAUCAGGAGCCACCUCCGGAGUACCGGGAAGUAAGACAGGCACAGCUGGAGUGCCCUCUGCUACAACAAUUGCCCCUGGGAGCUCCAACUCAGAGGCCACGACUUCUUUAGGAGAAAGUGGAAAAACAAGAGUUGAAACAAUCACAGGUACUACUGAGGGUAAAACUCUGGCAGCUGGAAGUGCCCACACAGAGGCCACAACUUUCUCAGGAGGCAGCGGGAGCACCCGAGCAGGACCACUGGGUGGCGCUUCUGGUACAUCAGGAGGAUAUGUCCCUGGAAGGGAAACAGAGCCCACAACUUCCAUUGAAGAAACUGGAACUUCCAGAACUAUAUUCAAAACUGUAGGCAUCACUUCAGCCCCAGGGAGGCAAGCAGGCACCUCUGUGGUGGCGCCUAGCACAACAGUUGCCCCUGGAAGUUUCAGCACAGCAGCCACAACUUCUCCUGGAGCAAGUGGAAUGACUGGGGUUAGAACCACUUCAAAGACUACAACUUCCCUAGGUGGAACUGGCACCACUAGAACUGAAAUAAAAUCAGGAGCCACCACUGGAGCACCAGGAAUUAAGACAGAUAUCAUGGGAGAAUCUUCUAGAACGACCAUUCUAUCUGGAAGUUCUAACACAGAGGCCACAAAUUCCAUUGAAGAGACUGGUACUUCUGGAACUGGAUUCAAAACUGCAGGCAUCACUGCAGCACCAGGAAAGCAAGCAGGCACCUCUGGGGUGGCACCUGGCACAACAGUUGCCCCUGGAAGUUUCAGCACAGCAGCUACAACUUCUCCUGGAGCAAGUGGAGUGACUGGCACUGGACCCACUGCAGAGACCACAACUUUCCUAGGAGGAAGUAGCACCACUGGAGCAGAAAUAAAAUCAGGAGCCACCACUGGAGCACCAGGAAGUAAGACAGGCACAGCUAAAGUGCUCUCUGGUACGACAGUUGCCUCUGGGAGCUCCAACUCAGAGGCUACAACUUUCUCUGGAAUCACUGAAGCAGUAACAGUCCCAAGUAAAAAUGGAUCUAUGACCACUGCACUGGGGAGCCAACUCUCCAGCAGUCAAACAGUGAUUCCAGGUUCCAGUGGCACCAUCUCUCACACAACUGUUGCACCUGGAAGUUCUGUUACAGGAACCACCACUGGUGCAUCAGAUGAUCAAGUCACUGGAAGUAAAACAGGCACUACUGGUGUGGCCUUGAGCACAACUGUUGCACCUGGAAGUUCCAGUACAGAAGCCACAACUUCCACAGGAGUCCAUAGAACCACUGUAGUGGGACAGAAGACAGGAGCUACCACUAGAGGGUCAGCAAAGCAAGGAACUAGAAGCACAAUAGAAGCUACGACGUCCUUUAGAGGCACUGGGACCACAGGAAGUGGAAUGAAUACAGGUACUACUGGAGUGGUCUCUGGCAACACCAUCUCACCUAGCAGUUUCAACACAGAAGCUACCAGUGGCACAUCUGAGAGGCCAAACCCUGGAAGUGAAAUAGGCACCACUGGCAUAGUCUCUGGCACAACAGUUGCACCUGGAAGUUCCAACACAGAAGCCACAACUUCUUUGGGCAAUGGUGGAACCACUGAGGCUGGAAGUAAAAUAGUUACCACUGGGAUAACUACUGGCACGACCAUUGUACCUGGGAGUUUCAACACAAAGGCUACCACUUCUACAGACGUUGGAGUUGCCACUGGAGUUGGAAUGGCAACUGGGAUCACCAACAUAAUUUCAGGGAGAAGCCAACCUACUGGAAGUAAAACAGGCUACACUGUAACAGGCUCUGGAACAACAGCCUUACCUGGAGGUUUCAGAACAGGCAAUACCCCAGGAUCAACGGGAGUCACCAGCAGCCAAGAAGGAACCACUGUGGUAUCAAGUGGAAUCACUGGAAUCCCAGAAACUUCCAUCUCAGGUCCUUCCAAGGAAGCAUCUGACAAAACCACUGCUCCUGGACCUCCUACCACAGUCACUGCUUCCACAGGAGUCAAAGAAACUUCUGAAACUGGAGUGCAAACAGGCUCCACCUUGGUUACAGCUGGAGUGCCAACAAGACCACAAGUAUCCCAGCCAGAAACCACUGUCGUGGCAACCAGAGAAGUAGAAACCGAAAAUAAAACAGAAUGUCUAGCCUCACUUCCACCAGCUCCAGUUUGUCACGGUCCAUUGGGAGAAGAGAAAUCUCCUGGAGACAUAUGGACUGCCAAUUGCCACAGAGGUACCUGUACUGAUGCAAAGACUAUAGACUGUAAACCUGAGGAGUGCCCUUCUCCACCCACAUGCAAAACCGGCGAGAAGCUUGUGAAGUUCCAAUCUAAUGACACCUGCUGUGAAAUCGGAUACUGUGAACCAAGAACAUGUUUAUUUAACAAUACUGACUAUGAGAUUGGUGCUUCAUUCGAUGACCCCAGCAACCCCUGUGUCUCCUACUCCUGCAAAGACACGGGCUUUGCUGCAGUAGUCCAGGACUGCCCAAAGCAAACCUGGUGUGCAGAAGCAAACAGAAUCUAUGAUUCAAAAAAAUGUUGCUAUACAUGUAAGAAUAAUUGCAGAUCUUCCCUUGUAAAUGUGACUGUUAUCUACAGUGGUUGCAAGAAAAGAGUUCAGAUGGCAAAAUGCACAGGGGAAUGUGAAAAGACUGCCAAGUACAAUUAUGAUAUCUUACUCUUGGAACAUUCAUGCCUUUGCUGCCGAGAAGAAAACUAUGAACUCAGAGACAUUGUACUUGACUGUCCUGAUGGCAGUACAAUCCCUUACCAAUACAAGCAUAUCACGACCUGCUCUUGUUUAGACAUAUGCCAACUAUAUACGACCUUCAUGUACAGUUAAUGCUGACAUCACCUUCCCAGUUUUAACAGGCCUGGUAUUUAUUUUAUAAGUGAGGAAAAAUAAUCAUUUAAAAAGUGAGAAUAAACUAAACAAUGUGAGAAUAACUCAAAA